GAUUUUCUUCCGCCAUCCGGCUAAAUAGUCCCAUGUGCACUUUGUUCCAUGGAUAAAUAAACACUAGGAACGCAUUUCCACCCUAGAUUUCAGCAGAAAUGCUGAAUGUAAAGGAAUAUUUGAGUAAAGUGAGUUGCCGUUCUUGAAGCCCGUCUCCUAAGGAUUCUCCCGGUGUCCGCGUAGGGAUCUCAUGCUAUAUAGGAGGGCCCUGCCAGGCACCGUCUCCUCUCUCCGGUCCGUGCCUCCAAGAUGACAAAGAAAAGAAGGAACAAUGGUCGUGCCAAAAAGGGCCGCGGCCACGUGCAGCCUAUUCGCUGCACUAACUGUGCCCGAUGCGUGCCCAAGGACAAGGCCAUUAAGAAAUUCGUCAUUCGAAACAUAGUGGAGGCCGCAGCAGUCAGGGACAUUUCUGAAGCGAGCGUCUUCGAUGCCUAUGUGCUUCCCAAGCUGUAUGUGAAGCUACAUUACUGUGUGAGUUGUGCAAUUCACAGCAAAGUAGUCAGGAAUCGAUCUCGUGAAGCCCGCAAGGACCGAACACCCCCACCCCGAUUUAGACCUGCGGGUGCUGCCCCACGUCCCCCACCAAAGCCCAUGUAAGGAGCUGAGUUCUUAAAGACUGAAGACAGGCUAUUCUCUGGAGAAAAAUAAAAUGGAAAUUGUACUUAAUAUUGCAUGUUAAGUGUAUCUGUGCCAGAUAAGGUGGGGAUUUUGUGUGUUAGACCAAGUGUGAAGUGACACACAUUAUUUUCAUGGGGAAGAAAGCUUAUUCAUGUAAUUUAAUUUUUUUCUUUUUUUUUUUUUUUUUUUUGAGACGGAGUCUUUGUCGCCCAAGCUGAAUUGCAGUGGCGUGAUCUCAGCUCACUGCAACCUCCGUCUCCCGGGUUCAAGUGAUUCUCCUGCCUCAGCUUCUUGAGUAGCUGGGAUUACAGGUGUCUGCCACCAUGCCUGGUUAAUUUUUGUAUUUUUGGUAGAGAUGGGGUUUCACUAUGUUGUCCAGGCUGGUCUUGAACUUCUGACCUCAGUUAAUCCACCAGCCUUGGCCUCCCAAAGUGCUGGGAUUACAGGCUUGAGCCACCUCGCCUAGCUAUUUAUGUAAAUUAAACUUUAAUUGUGGUCGUAUGGUUGGCCUCACAAUUCGCA